UUUUCAGAAAAUAAAUACUUAACAGAGGAAUUUUAAAAUUGUGUAAUUCUUGAUGUUUUAGUUUCAAUUUCUUUUAAGAAUCUUACCCUUUUUGUUUCUUUUCCAACACUUUAUUCAUUGAUAACUCACUAACAUUUUCAUCCUGAGAAAAUUAAAUAAAUAGAACAUCUAAAAGUCAGCUUUGUAAUUUAUUAAAAAAUCUAGGGGAGAACGUACAGCAAGAUGGCCAAAUAGAAGACUUUAUGCUGUGGGAACUCCAAAUUUAAGAACUACCUACACACACAAAAAAAACACCUACAUAAGAAUCAGAAAUCAGGUGAGCACUCACAGUACCUGGUUUUAACUUCAAAUGACUGAAAGAGGCACUGAAGAGGGUAGGAAAGACAGUCUUAAAUUACCAGUGCCACCCUUCCCCUAUCUCCUGGCAGUGGCCAUGUGACAUGGAGAGAGAAUUGUGCACUUAGGGGAGGGAGAAUGCAGUGACUGUUGGACUUUGCAUUGAACUCGGUCUUGCCCUGUCAUAGCAGAGAGCAAAACCGGGCCAAAUGCAUCUCAUGCCUGCCCACAGAAAGAGCAUUUAGACCAGACCUGUCCAGAGGACAAUCACCCAUCCCAGUGGUUGGAACCUGAGUUCUGGCAAGCCUCAUUACCACAGGACUUUGGGGCUCUAUAUAAACUUAAAAGACUGUCUAGGCCACAAUGACUUCAACUCCUAGGCAAGCCCUAGUGCAGAGUUGGGCUCAGACCAGUGGACUUGGGUGGCAUGUGACCUACUGAGACACCAGCCAGGGCAGCUCAUGGGGUAUUUGUGCCACUGCUCUCCCAACCCUUGGCAGCACAGCUCAUGGCUCUGAAAGGAACCCCUUCCAUCUGCUUGAGGAGGAGAGAAGAAAGAUCAAAUAGGUCUUUGUCUUGCAUCUUGGACAGCAGCUCAGCCACAAUAGGAUAGGGCGCUAGUUAGAUUUAUGAGACCCUUAUUCUAGGCCCUAGCUCCUGGAUGACAUUUCUAGACACAUCCUGGGCUAGAAGCGAACCUGGUGCCUUGAAGGCAAGGAUGCAGUCCCGGCAGGAUCUAUCACCUACUGACUGAAGAGCCCUUGGGCCCUGAAUAACCAGCAGCAAUACCCAGAUGGUACACUGUGGGUCUUGGCUGAGACUCUGAGAUGUGCUGGAUUCAGGUGAAACCCAGGGCAUCCCCAGCUGUGGUGGCUGUGGUGAGAAACCCCUGCAUGAGAAAAGCAGAGGGAAAAGUAAAGGGUAAUUUGUCUUGCACCUUAGGUACCAGCUCAUCCACAAUGAAGUAGAACACCAAGCAGCUUGUGGGGUCAUUGAUUCCAGGCUUUGGCUCUUAGUUGGCAUUUCUAGACCUGCCCUGGGCCAGAGGGAAACCCAUUGCACUGAAAGGUGAGUCCCAGGCCUGGCAGCAUUUGUGGCAAGCUGACUGAAGAGCCCUUGGGCUUUAAGGAACAUUGACAGUGGCCUGGUAGUACUCCCUGUAGGACUGUGGUGGUGGUGACCACAGGCAGAGACUCCUUUGCCUGUGGAAAGGGAAGGGAAGAGUGGGAAGGACUGUGUCUGGUGGUUUGAGUGCCAGCUCAGCUGCAGUGGACUAGAACACCAGGUGGAUUUCUAAGGUUUUUUACUCUACUCCCUGGCUCCUAGAUGGCAUCUCUGGACCCACCCAGGGCUGGAGGGAUCCUGCUACCCUGAAGGGAAUGACACAAGUCUGACUGGCUUCACAGUCUGCUCUUUGCAGAGCCCUAGGGCCUUGAGCAAACAUAGGUGGAAGCCAGAUAGUGGUUACAGUGGGCCUUGGGUGAGACUCAGGGAUAUACUGGUGUCAGUUCUGACCCCCAGCAUAGUCCCAGUGGUGGUGGCCACAGGGGUGCAUUUGUCACUCCAUCCCCAGCUCCAGAAGGCUCAGCAAAGAGAGAGAGACUCUGUUUGUUUGGGAGAAGGAAAGAAAACAAGAGUCUCUGCCUGGUAAUCCAGAGAAUUCUUCCGGAUCUUAUCCAAGACUGCCCAGGCAGUAGUUCUAGAAGUCGGCAAGAACCCCAGUCUUACUGGACUUGGGGUGCCCACUAAUGCAGAUAUGGACUAGAUCACAACACCCAAGUCCUUUCAAAUACCGGAAAGUCUUGGGCUGAAUCAAUCCUACUGCCUUAGCAUCUUUGUACCCAUCUUCUCAAGAAGAUUGGGUACAAACAAUCCCAGACUGCAAAGACAAAAAUAAAUAUCUAACUUUUGUAUUCCCAGACACCAGCAAACAUCCAUAAGGAUCAAGACUAUCCAAGUGAUAGGUUACGCUUUGUGUCCCCACCCCAGACUCAUCUUGAAUUAUAAUCCCCAUAAUCUCCACGUGUCAAAAGAGAGACCAGGUGGAGGUAAUUGAAUCAUGGGGGUGGUUUCUCCCAUGCUGCUCUCAUGAUAGUGAGUGAGUUCUCAUGAAAUCUGAUGGUUUUGUAAGGGGCUUUUUCCCCGUUCGCUUGGCACUUCUCCUUCCUGCUGCCUUGUGAAGAAGGUGCCUUGCUUCCCCUUCACCUUCCACCAUGAUUAUUAGUUUCCAGAGGCCUCCCCAGCCAUGCUGAGUUGUGAGUCAAUUAAAUCUCUUUCCUUUAUUACUCAGUCUUGAGCAGUUCCUUAUAGAAGUAUGAAAACAGGAUAAUAUACCAAGAAAACAUGACUUCAUCAAACAAACGAAAUGAGGCACCUGGGAUCAAUACUGCAGAAACAGAUAUGUAGCCUUUCAGACAGAGAAUUCCAAAUAACUGUUUUGAGGAAACUCAAAGAAAUUCAAGAUAACAUGGAGAAGGAUUUCAGAAUUCUAUCAGAGAAAUUUAACAAAGUGAUUGAAAAAAUAAAAAAGAAUCAAGCAGAAAUUCUGGAAUGAAAAAUGCACUGGAGUCCCCUCAUAGCAGAAUUGAUCAAGCAGAAGAAGGAAUUAGUGAGCUUGAAGACAGGCUAUUUGAAAAUACAUAGUCAGGGCGGGUGUGGUGGCUCAUGCCUGUAAUCCCAGCACUUUAGGAGGCUGAGGUGGGAGGAUCACCUAAUGUCAGGAAUUUGAGAUGAGCCUGGCCAAUAUGGUGGAACCCUGUCUCUACUAAAAAUACAAACAUUAGCCAGGCAUGGUGGCACAUGCCGGUGAUCCCAGCUACUUGGGAGGCUGAGUCAGGGGAAUCGCUUGACCCCGGGAGGCGGAGGUUGCUGUGAAUCGAGAUCACGCCACUGCACUCCAGCCUGGUGACAAAGCGAGACUCCAUCUCGAAAAAAAAAAAAAAGAAAAUACACAGAGGAGAUAAAAGAAUAAAAAACAAUGAAGCAUGCCUACAAGAUUAAUGAAAUAGCCUCAAAAGGGAAAAUGUAGGAGUUAUUGGCCUUAAACAGGAGUUAGUGAAAAAGACAGGAGUACAAAGUUUAUUCAAAGGGAAAAUAACAGAGAACUUUUCAAACCUAGCAAAAGAUAACAAUAUUCAACUAUGAGAAAGUUGUAGAACACCAAGCAGGUUUAACCCAAAAAAGACAACCUGAAGGCAUUUAACAAACUCCCAAGGGUCAAGGAUAAAGAAAGGACCCUAAAAGCAGCAAGAGAAAAGAAACAAAUAACAUACAAUGGAGCUUCAAUAUGCUGGCAGCAGACUUUUCAGUGGAAACUUUACAGGCUAGGAGAUAGUGGCAUGACAUACUUAAAGUGCUGAAGGAAAAAACAACAACAGACUUUUGCCCUGGAAUAAUAUAUCCUGCAAAAAUAUCCUUCAAACAUGAAGGAGAAAUGCUUUGACAGGCAAACAAAAGCUGGAGAUUUCAUCAACACCAUACCUAUCCUACAAGAAGUCAUAAAUGGAAUACUUAAAUCAGAAAAAGGAUAUUAAUGAGUAAUAAAUCAUCUGAAGGUACAAAAGUCACUGGCAAUAGUAAGUACACAGAAUGACAUACAAUAUUGUAAUACCGUAACAGUGGUAUACAAACUACUCUUAAGUAGAAAGACUUAAAGAUGAGCCAAUCAAAAAAUAACUAUAAAAAGUUUUCAAGACAUAGUAUAAUAAGAUAUAAACAACAAAAAGUUAAAAACAGGCUGGACAAAGUUAAAUAAUUUUUAUCAGUUUUGUUUUUGCUUGUUUAUGCAAGCAGUGUUGUUAAUCCAGUUAAAAUAAUGGGUUAUAAGAUAGUUAUAUCCCAUAUAUAUAAUGGGUUGCAACAUUCAUUGUAACCUCAAAUCAAAAACCAUACAGUGGCUACGCAAAAAAUAAAAAGAAAGGAAUAAAAUUUUCGUUUUAUUUUAGGAGAAAAGGUAAGAGAAAAUUACCUUCACUACAAGGAAAACAAGAAAGAAUGAAGGAAGGAAAAGAAGACCACAAAAUAACCAGGAAACCAACAACAAAAUGAACAGCUCUUUAGAUCUGGUGAAGAUGAUGAGGUCAAGAGGAGUACUCCAGAGAAGAAUGGAAAAGAAAUGUUGGAGCAGACAUUACAGAAGGUCACUGAGUUGGAAAAUCGGCUGAAAUCUUUUGAGAAAAGGUCGAGAAAAUUAAAAGAAGGGAAUAAAAAAUUAAUGAAAGAAAAUGAUUUUCUGAAAUCCCUCUUAAAACAGCAACAAGAAGAUACAGAGACCAGAGAAAAAGAGCUAGAACAGAUAAUAAAGGGGAGUAAAGAUGUAGAAAAAGAAAAUACUGAACUUCAAGUAAAAAUCAGUGAGCUGGAGACAGAAGUCACUUCCCUGAGGAGACAAGUGGCAGAAGCUAAUGCAUUGAGAAAUGAAAAUGAAGAGCUGAUCAACCCAAUGGAGAAAUCACACCAGUCAGCAGACAGAGCUAAAUCCGAGAUGGCCACCAUGAAAGUGAGAUCUGGACGAUAUGAUUGUAAGACAACUAUGACCAAGGUUAAAUUUAAAGCUGCGAAGAAAAAUUGCUCUGUGGGUCGUCACCACACUGUUCUCAAUCAUUCCAUCAAGGUUAUGAGCAAUGUGUUUGAGAACCUCAGCAAGGACGGCUGGGAGGAUGUGAGUGAAAGCAGCAGUGAUUCUGAAGCACAGACCUCUCAAACUUUGGGAACAAUUAUUGUAGAAACAUCCCAGAAAAUAAGUCCUACGGAAGAUGGAAAAGACCAGAAAGAAAGUGAUCCAACAGAAGACAGCCAAACACAAGGAAAAGAAAUAGUACAGACAUAUUUAAAUAUAGAUGGCAAGACCCCAAAGGACUAUUUUCAUGAUAAGAAUGCCAAAAAACCAACUUUUCAAAAGAAGAAUUGCAAGAUGCAAAAGAGUUCACAUACAGCAGUUCCUACUAGAGUCAACAGAGAAAAGUACAAAAAUAUAACUGCCCAGAAAUCAAGUAGCAAUAUUAUUUUAUUACGAGAACGGAUUAUAUCCUUGCAACAACAAAACAGUGUACUUCAGAAUGCCAAGAAAACAGCAGAAUUGUCUGUUAAAGAAUAUAAAGAAGUUAAUGAAAAGCUCCUCCAUCAACAGCAAGUAUCCGAUCAACGAUUUCAGACAAGCAGGCAGACAAUAAAGAAGCUAAAUUUGGAUUUGGCUGGGCUUCGGAAAGAAAAAGAAGAUUUACUAAAGAAAUUGGAGUCCUCAUCUGAAAUCACAAGUUUGGCAGAAGAAAAUUCCCAGGUAACAUUUCCACGGAUACAAGUUACAUCACUUAGUCCUUCAAGGAGCAUGGAUUUGGAAAUGAAGCAAUUGCAGUAUAAACUAAAGAAUGCUACUAAUGAACUCACUAAACAGUCAUCAAAUGUGAAGACUUUGAAAUUUGAACUCCUAGCAAAAGAAGAACACAUAAAGGAAAUGCAUGAAAAGAUAUCUCGAAUGGAGAGGGAUAUAACUAUGAAAAGACAUUUGAUAGAGGACUUGAAAUUUCGACAGAAAGUAAAUUUGGAAAGUAACAAGAGUUUUAGUGAAAUGUUACAAAAUCUUGAUAAAAAGGUAAAGACAUUAACUGAAGAAUGUUCCAACAAGAAGGUAUCAAUUGAUUCACUAAAGCAAAGACUUAACGUUGCUGUAAAAGAAAAGUCACAGUAUGAACAGAUGUAUCAGAAAUCUAAAGAGGAGUUAGAAAAAAAGGAUCUCAAGCUUACUCUCCUAGUAUCAAGAAUAAGUGAGACUGAAUCUGCAAUGGCAGAAAUUGAAACAGCAGCAUCUAAGCAGCUUCAAGAAUUAGCAUUGCAAAGUGAACAGGUCCUAGAAGGUGCACAGAAGACAUUGCUGUUAGCCAAUGAAAAAGUAGAAGAGUUCACCACAUUUGUGAAGGCUUUGGCCAAAGAGUUGCAAAAUGAUGUCCAUGUGGUAAGGCGACAAAUAAGAGAGCUUAAAAAAAUGAAGAAAAACAGGGACGCCUGUAAAACCUCAACCCAUAAAGCCCAGACCUUGGCAGCUUCUAUCCUGAACAUUUCACGGUCAGAUUUAGAGGAAAUAUUAGACACAGAAGAUCAAGUGGAAAUUGAAAAAACAAAAAUUGAUGCUGAAAAUGACAAGGAAUGGAUGUUGUACAUUCAGAAACUUCUUGAAGGACAGCUUCCUUUUGCCUCAUAUUUACUAGAAGCAGUACUGGAAAAAAUAAAUGAAAAAAAGAAACUAGUUGAAGGAUAUUUCACAAUUAUGAAAGAUAUUAGAUGAUAUUAAAAUGGAGAGCUUUAUUGCAAAUGUGAAAACUUUUUAUGUGGUGUGAUUGGAAUACAUGCAUUGCAAUCCUGACACGGUAUCUGCUCCAACUAUCAAUAGUCAGGUUCAAUACCAAAAUAAGAAGUCUCUGAAAAUAAUUAAUUGCUGAACAAGUGAAACUAAUUAAGUACAUAGCCAUUUAAAAGGAAAUAGUGUAGCAUCUGAUGGUCGAAUACAAAUAUUGCCACAAAUCAGUGCAAACUUAAAAAUGAUUUUCCUUCUAGUGCAUUAAAAGAAACUGAGCAGGCUUGGUACACACAAAUUGGCCUGAGCAUAAGAAGAAAAAGUAUCAACUAAGGAUUUAAUGUUUUACGUUUCAUGAAGAAACUAGACUUUUUACAUAAAACUGCUAUAGAUGGCCAUAAGUGGUCCAGGGAGCAACAGAUUUGUAGUAUGAGCAAAUAUAAAAUGAAGCAUCAUAACUUGAGCAUUUAUUGAAAUAAAUUGUGUGGUCCAAUUGAAUCUGUUCUCAUUGAUGUGCUGGUUUAUGUAGGAGAUACUGUGUAUUUCUACAACUCUUUGGCAAAAACAAAAACAUUUUCUUCUUCUCUCUCUUAACUUCACAAUACUAUACGUUGUGUAGUCAUAUAAAUUUGCAGGGAACCACAAACCCAAUGUAUAAAAUUAGGCUCUAUUUAACAGAACUACUACUGUGGUCAGCUAAUUUAAGUUACAUUCUUAACCAUGAUGUCAUCCUUAUUUAGAUUCCUGGACAUUCCCACCUCAUUUCACCUCUUCACCGUGUUCCUGCCAUACCCUUUUUGGUUCCUCUAAUUCACCAUACUGGUGCCUGCCUCCCACAUUUGCCCUUGGUCUUCUCUCUUUCUAGAAUACUCUGCACUCAACUUUCCUCAUGGCUGGCUCCUUGUCAUCAUUCAGCUCCACCUUCCCCGGUCCCUCAGAGACACAUUCUCUGACCAGCUUACUAUUUUAUUUCCUCAUAGCACAAAAUUAUCUAUCUGUUCAUGUAUUUGUUUUCUUGUUUAUUUUCUUCUUUUCCCUCUUUAGUAUGUAGGUCCCAUGAGAUUAAGGCAAGGGUUGGCAGAUUAUAGCCUGCAGGGCGAAUCUGGCCUGCCACCUGUUUUGUAUGGCCCACAAGCUAAGAAUGGUUUUUGCCUUAUUAAAUGGUUUUUAAAAAAUCAAAAGGAGAAUAAUAUUUUGUAGCAUGUGAAAAUUAUAUAAAAUUCAAAUUUUGGUGUCUGUUAAUAAAGUUUUAUUGGAACACA